ACAGACUUCUGACAGCUGGACUUUUAGCCACGGAGACUCGGGAUGUGAAGGAUUUCUCGUGUCUCCUUUUUUUGCCUCAGGAGUUAGCAGCACUUCUUCCACGUGGGCAGCCACCAGAGCAGGCUUCUCAAGUUGAGAGAAAUUUGUGCCUUUGAACUCCAUGGCAUAUUCAUCCUCUAACAGCGACAUAGAGGACGACAGCUCCAAAUCCAAUUCCAACCUGAGCCUCUCUGUGGGCUAUUUCCCCUGUGAGGACACCCCCUGUGAGGACACAACCUCCUGGGAAGAUGCACCUUCCAAGGGUCCUUCCAUCCACUUUCUGCCUCCCGUCCAAGGGGCAUGGGGGACUGAAAGGAUAGGGAGACGCAUGAAGAGACAAGACCAAAUUCAGGAUGAACCAGAGCAGUUUUGCAAACUAAGCAUCUUCCUGGCCUGGGACGUGGACAUUGGCUCCGAUAACACAGACUCAAGAGCUAAUAGGCUUCUAAAUGGAGACAACCUGUGGAUAGACAAGUUACCAAAAGAGAGAACAAAACUGUCUGUUGGCAAACUGAAUAAUCUUGUGCAAGAGUUUCAGAUAUUUCUAGAAAAUCUGAAAGAUGAUGACGCUGUAUUUCCUGAAACUGCUCAGCAAGAUUUCCAGCUAUCCAGCGGCUCCCCUCCGGAAAUGGUUCAGAUGAUAAGCCAGGCAACCGCCAGCCAAAGGACAAGCGCUCCAGAGAUCUCCUCAAUCCUGUCAGAGCAGCCAGAGAAGGAUGACACUCCUUCACACACACAGGCCCAGUGCUGCCUGAACUUUGGGUGGGCCUUCAGCUGGCUGAGGCAGCGUAUCCUCCCCUCUCUGCUGAGGAGGGAUCACCCUGUGAAUGCCACCAAAAGUCCCCAUCGGUCAGCACCAACGAAAAGACUCUUUCACAGAGGCAAGAGAAUUCAACCUCAAGAAACCCUUGAAUUAGGACAUCCCAUAUAGACAGAUUUUUAAACUUUUUGGAAAGUUUAAAAUAAUCCAUAAUAAGGAUUCCAUUAAUAAUCCCCAUCAGUUUGUUUUUUCCUCAAUAAACAAAAUAAAUGCUCUUGUUACCCCACA